GGAAGCGGCAGCGCGGCGCGACCCGGCGGGCGGGCUCUGGGCGCGGGAAUCCCGGCGGAUCCCGGGCGGGCGGAUGACCCCCAGCCCUACCCUUGGUGCCGCCUCCUCCUCUCUCCUUUCUCCUCCGGCAGCCAGCGCGCCUGUGUCCUCUCUAGGAAGGGGUAGGGGAGGGGCGUCUGGAGAGGACCCCCCGCGAAUGCCCACGUGACGUGCAGUCCCCCUGGGGCUGUUCCGGCCUGCGGGGAACAUGGGCGUGCUCAGGGUCGGACUGUGCCCUGGCCUUACCGAGGAGAUGAUCCAGCUUCUCAGGAGCCACAGGAUCAAGACAGUGGUGGACCUGGUUUCUGCAGACCUGGAAGAGGUAGCUCAGAAAUGUGGCUUGUCUUACAAGGCCCUGGUUGCCCUGAGGCGGGUGCUGCUGGCUCAGUUCUCGGCUUUCCCCGUGAAUGGCGCUGAUCUCUACGAGGAACUGAAGACCUCCACUGCCAUCCUGUCCACUGGCAUUGGCAGUCUUGAUAAACUGCUUGAUGCUGGUCUCUAUACUGGAGAAGUGACUGAAAUUGUAGGAGGCCCAGGUAGCGGCAAAACUCAGGUAUGUCUCUGUAUGGCAGCAAAUGUGGCCCAUGGCCUGCAGCAAAACGUCCUAUAUGUAGAUUCCAAUGGAGGGCUGACAGCUUCCCGCCUCCUCCAGCUGCUUCAGGCUAAAACCCAGGAUGAGGAGGAACAGGCAGAAGCUCUCCGGAGGAUCCAGGUGGUGCAUGCAUUUGACAUCUUCCAGAUGCUGGAUGUGCUGCAGGAGCUCCGAGGCACUGUGGCCCAGCAGGUGACUGGUUCUUCAGGAACUGUGAAGGUGGUGGUUGUGGACUCGGUCACUGCGGUGGUUUCCCCACUUCUGGGAGGUCAGCAGAGGGAAGGCUUGGCCUUGAUGAUGCAGCUGGCCCGAGAGCUGAAGACCCUGGCCCGGGACCUUGGCAUGGCAGUGGUGGUGACCAACCACAUAACUCGAGACAGGGACAGCGGGAGGCUCAAACCUGCCCUCGGACGCUCCUGGAGCUUUGUGCCCAGCACUCGGAUUCUCCUGGACACCAUCGAGGGAGCAGGAGCAUCAGGCGGCCGGCGCAUGGCGUGUCUGGCCAAAUCUUCCCGACAGCCAACAGGUUUCCAGGAGAUGGUAGACAUUGGGACCUGGGGGACCUCAGAGCAGAGUGCCACAUUACAGGGUGAUCAGACAUGACCUGUGCUGUUGUUUGGGAAACAGGGAAGCAUUGGGGACCCCUCCCAACUUUUCUUCCCAGUAACGCCUGCUGUUUACUGCCACCUGGCACUGGUGACUACAGACGUUCUCAGGCUGGCCAGAAGAGACAUCUUGGGUUCCUUGGCCUCACUCUCUGUAAGCAUAUAAACCACAGGCGAAAGAGGAUGCUGCAUUGCGAGGACCCAGAAAUUCAUACUGGUGCCACGUUUCCUUCCCUUAUUUCUAACGUGUAUGUUUCUGGUGGAAACCAAGUUCACCCUGGCUGGGAGCAUCUCUGAUGAGGCAUGCUGGCGACUGGAUGGAUAAUCCUGUGCAUCACCAUUGUGUCCUGUGCUCCCUCCUAGCGCAGUGGCCAAGCCGGGAAAGCCUCUAACUUGCCUUUGCUGCUGCUGCCUUUUUUUUCUUUUGUCUCUGCCUUUCCAUUUGUUAGAUGGGGGCCCACUCUUCCUUAGCUCUGUCUCUGAGUUACUGGGUGGAAAUAAGCUUAUAAAUGAAAUACUCUUCUUCAUCUCUGUUUUGCUCUUAAAAAUAUAAAAAGGCAAUUCCCCGAGCCCUAGAGCCACCUGAUUUCCCCUUAGAAGGCUGUUUUUCAGUUUCCCCCAGUGAGGCCCAAAGAACAGUUUAUUCCUCCUUUCCUCUUGCUGAUUUGGUUUCAGACCUGCCUGCAUCACCAUGACUAGGUGAGAACGUGUGGGCUCGCUGCAGUUCCAGGGAUAUAAUUUAACAGAAAGGGAGGGUAUGACCUGCUCCUGGUGAAUCCAGCCACUCAUUUAAUAUGCAUGGUGCCCUGUGGGGCCCCUCCACAGUACAGCAUAACCAGAGGUGCUGAACCAUGGCCUUGCCCAUAAACAGACAGAGGAGAAUUUGCACAGUAAAUAGAGCCAGCUGGGAAAAUUGAUGCUGACGUAAAUAAUACAUGGCAAAUCUAGUCCUUUAUGCAGAAAUUCAUUGCUGGUGGCUCCAAGAUGCAAUAUAAUUACACCUCUCUUCCUGCCAGCUGUACCACAGCUAGUGCCCUAGUGUAUGAAAUAAUCCCUCUGUCUUUCACCAGCACUGUGGCCAUCCGUCUGAGAGCCAUGACCCUGGCUGGGAGGGGACGAAGACACCAGGGAAUGGAAAAUAAAAGGAAAAGUACAGAAAUGAUCAGGAUUGGUUACUGGCCACAUCUUUUAAAGGAAGGUCAUCUUUCUUGGUUAGAGAGCCUGUUGUGUAAUUAAUCAGUUAUGUCUUGGCUGCAGGAAAGGAGGGUCCGAGUUACACUCAGAAAGUAAUGACAUUUAGAGGUGAUGAAUGCAACAGGGAUAGAAUCAUGGAGGAUUGGGAAGGAGUGGCAAACUGGCACCAGGGUGUUGGAUUCAGGACAGGGUUGGUAAGCCUAAGCCUGGGGGAAUCCUAGCGCUUGCUUUCACAGAAGACCUCAGGAGAAAUUAAUCUUCAGUAUCUUUAUACCAUGGGUGAUUGGCACAUUCCUGCAACCACAGUAAGAUGCAAUACAUGAAGCUGGAAAUUGCAAAUUCUUGCCACUCAAGGUACUAUUUGGGCAUCUUCAGCCCACAGCAGACAUGACCAAUCGGGCACAAGCACUCUUUUUUGUGGAAGUCAAAGUGUUUUUAGAAGUUUUUCUCAAUAUAGCACUCCAGGGGGCCACUACCAGUCAGUUGGAGUUGGUAUUCAAGGUGGAGUCUGGUUGCCGUCUCUGCCCUGUUCCCAUUAUGUAGUGAGUUCAGGUACUUAAUACCUAACUGAGGACCCUAGGACUGCAGUUUGAGAUCAUCUGGGGCCAGGCACAGUGGCUCACACCUAUAAUGGUAGCACUUUGGGAGCCUGAGGCGGGAGGAUCACUUGAGCCCAGGAGUUUAACAGUUUAAAAUCAGCCUGGGCAACAUGAUGAGACAUCGUUUCUACAAAAAAAUUUUUUAAAUUAGCUAGGCAUUGUGAUGUGCACCUGUGGUCCCUGCUACUUGGGAGCCUGAGGCAGGAGAAUCGCUUGAACCUUGGAGGUUGUGGCUGCAGUGAGCCCUGAUCGCACCACUACACCCCAGCCUGGGUAACAGAGCAAGACCCUGUCUCAAGGAAAAAAAAAAUCAUCUGGCCCAUCCUGUUACUUAACAGAGAAGGUACCUGAGGCUCAAAAAGGAUGACUGACAGUCCUAGUGGCAGAAUGGAGGUGGGAUCUGGAACCCACAACUUGAUUCCUAGGACUCUUUUUUUUUUAAUUCCCACAUUGGCUGGGUGUGGUGGCUCACGCCUGUAAUCCCAGCACUUUGGGAGGCUGAGGUGGGUGGAUCACCUAAGGUCAGGAGUUCCAGACCAGCCUGACCAACAUGGUGAAACCCCGUCUGUACUAAAAAUACAAAAAUUAGCCAGGCAUGGUGGCCCAUUUCCUGUAAUCCCAGCUACUCAGGAGGCUGAGGCAGAAUCGCUUGAACCUGGGAGGCGGAGGUUGCAGGGAGCUGAGAUGGCGCCACUGCACUCCAGCCUGAGCGACAGAGUGAGACUCCGUCUCAAAAAAAAAAAAAAAAUGCAAAAAUUAGCCAGGCGUCGUGGCGCAUGUCUGUAAUCCCAGCUCCUCGAGAGGCUGAGUGGGGAGGAUCACUUGAGCCCAGGAGGCAGAGGUUGCAAUGACCUGCGAUCAUGCCACUGCACUCCAGCCUGGGCAACAGAGACUCUGUUUCAAAAAGAAAAAAAAAAUCCCCACAUUUUAUUUAAUUUUCAGUCCAUACAGUUCUAUUCCUGCUAGGGCUGUAACUCCAGCUGAAGGCACCACAGCUGUCACCCAAGGAGUUUCUGUGGCCAUGGGAAGGUGUUGCAUUCACUGCUACUUGAGACCACCACGUGACAUUCCUGCAGGCUGUGCCCCUCACAGCCAGCUUCAUCCUUUGGCUCCUCCUAGACCAGGACUUUGUCUUGCCUGCCUGCUGCCACUGCACUCUGUUCCGGCCACACCACACUGUGCAGUCCCCUGGUAGGACUUGGGCUAGGCUGGCUCUCCUGUCCAAGUGCCUUUUGCUCCCUUUGCUUAUGUGUCUGUCUCUGCCCAGCUCCCACUGUGUCUGGUGCACACCCACCCUGACAUCCUUUUUUAUGCCUCAGCUGUGAUCUAGAUAGAUGCUUACAGUAACUUCCCUGUAUUAGUUAUUCACUUGUACUUUCUGUUCACGUGUCUGCCUACAGGCUCCCACUUUUUGUCACUUUUUCUCUUUAUACAUUAUGGAAGCUCAGUAAUGAUUAAAUAGAUGAAUGAUGUUUUAAAAAUAUAUUUUAAAAAAGCAAAGGACUGGCUCUAUCUCAGGGGUUCCUUCCAUAAAGCGUCAACUUUCAAUUUCCCCUGCGGGGGUGGUUUGAGACCUGAGGGCACUCUCUAGUUCUUAGGAAAAAAAUAUACAUAUACAUAUACAUAUAUAUAUAUAUAUACACACACACACACACACAUAUACACACAUAUAUAUACAUAUAUAUACACACAUAUAUAUAUAUACACACAUAUAUAUACACACAUAUAUAUACACAUAUGAGCCAGGCGCAGUGGCUCACGCCUGUAAUCCCAGCACUUUGGGAGGCCAAAGUGGGCGGAUCACAAGGUCAGGAGUUCAAGACCAGCCUGGCCUAUAUAGUGAAACCCUGUCUCUACUAAAAAUACAAAAAUUAGCUGGGUGUGAUGGCUCGCAUCUGUAAUCCCAGCUACUUGGGAGGCUGAGGCAUGAGAAUCGCUUGAACCUGGGAGAUGGAGGUUGCAGUGAGCCGAGAUUGUGCCACUGUACUCUAGCCUGGGCAACAGAGUGAGACUCCAUCUAAAAAAUAUAUAUAUAUGUUCACACCCACAUCAUUGAGUCCCCAGAGUGUCUUCUUACAUAUCUUUUUACAGGGGACUAUUGUAUGCCCUUCGUCUGACAUCAGAUGAAAUUAAUGUUGAGAUCCUACUAUGUGCUAGCACUUGAUGGCCUUAAUUAAAAAUCAGGCAUUUGAAUUCCCAAGGACUCAGGCAAAGGUCCAUGUAUCAUUAAGGCUGCAAGUAACAAAACCUAGGCUUAAAGAAGUGUAAAUACUAGGGACACUUAUUUAUAUUUAUUUCUUUUAUGUUUCAAGACAGAGUCUUGCUCUGGAGUGCAGUGGCACAAUCACGGCUCACUGUACCCUCUACCUCCCAAGCUCAAGUGAUCCUCCCACUUCAGUCUCCCAAGUAGCUGGGACUACAGGUGUGUGCCACCACACCCAUCUAAGUUUUGUAUUUUUUGUAGAGACGGGGUCUCUGUACGUUGCCCAGGCUGGUCUUGAACUCCUGGGCUCAGGUGAUCUACCCGCCUUGACCUCCCAAAGUGCUAGGGAUUACAGUCAUGAGCCACCAUGCCUGGCAGGGACACUUAUUAUCUCUGAUAACAGGAAGUCUGAGGUUUGUUAAUUUAGUGGCUCAUUGUCAAAUGGCGUAGAGCCUUUGCAUCCUUCUGCUCUGUUCUUUUAUGUUGGUUUUGUCUUCAAGCUUGUUCCCCUUAUGAAAGCCUGGCUGCAGCCAUUUUGAGCAUCAAUCCAGACGUGACAAUAUCUACAGGCAGGAGAAGGAUCGCCUCCUGUGUGUCCUUUAAAGAACAAGGUGUUAACAUGCCAGGAACUGUGGCUCCUGACUGUAAUCCCAGUAAUUUGGGAAGCCAAAGUAGGAGGAUCGCCUGAGGCCAGGAGUUCCAGACCAGCCUGGGCAACAUAGCAAGACCCUAUCUCUAUAAAAUAAAAUAAUAAAAAUUAAGAAAACAAGGUGUUAAAAGACAAAAUUAAAGCAAAUAUAGUUUUGCAGAUUGUAAUUGACUUUUAUUUGCAAUUCUAGAAUUGGGCUGCCCUCAGAACCAGGACAGGUUCAGAGAAUUCCAGAGCUGCAACAUAGUCUGAAAGCAUUUAUGGUCAGAAAACAGAAAUGAGAUACAAAGACAACUAAUUGGUUACAGCUCUGCCUUUGCCUUAUUUGAAAAUGGUUUGAAUAGUUGGCUGCCUGGAACCCACUGAAGCUGAUGAUGUGAUUGGCUGAGCCUCAGCAAUCUGUUACAAAAGUAUACUCCUAAAUUAGGUUUUCAGUUAGUUUGCAUACUAAGGCUGCAGUUUGUUAAGGGCCCAAGUAAAGCCUCCUCAGGUCAAUUUUUUUUUUCUUUUUGAGAUGGAGUCUUGCUCUUGCUCAGGCUGGAGUGCAGUGGCGUGAUCUCAGCUCACUGCACCUCUGCCUCCCGGGUUCAAGUGAUUCUCCUGCCUCAGCCUCCUGAGUAGCUGGGACUACGACUACAGGCGCCUGCCACUAUGUCCGGCUAAUUUUUUGUAUUUUUAGUAGAGAUGGGGUUUCAUCAUGUUGGCCAUGGCUGGUCUCGAACUCCUGACCUCAGAUGAUCUGCCUGCCUCAGCCUCCCAAAGAACUGGGAUUAUAGGCAUGACCCACUGUGACUAGCCCUCAGGCCAAAUUUAGCUUUUGUUUGUUUGUUUGAGACGGAGUCUCUGUCACCUAGGCUGGAGUGCAGUGGCAUGAUCUUGGCUCACUGCAACCUCUGCUUCCUGGGUUCAAGCAAUUCUGCCGCAGCCUCCCGAGUAGCUGGGAUUACAAGCAUGCGCCCCCAUCCCCGGCUCUUUUUGUAUUUUUAGUAGAGAUGGGGUUUCACCAUGUUGGCCAGACUGGUCUCAAACUCCUGACCUCAGGUGAUUCACCUGCCUCUGCCUCCCAAAGUGCCUGGAUUACAGGCGUGAGACACCACACCCGACCCCAAAUUUAAUUUAACAAAGGACUAACUCAGAACUAACUUCCAACCAAAGCUGACUCACCUCAAAUCUCAUUGGUGCAGAAUUGCUUCAUACACCCAUGUGUAAUACAGUAACUGGCAAGAAAAAGGGACUGCUGUGAUUGACUCAAACCAACUAGGAAAUAGCCCUGGAGCUGAGGCUGGGGACAGGCUUUCCUGAAGCACAUGCUGGAGCCACUGAAAGAAAAAUGGGAGUUCUCCUUUCUACUAGAAAGGAGAGUGUGUGGAUGAACUGGAUGCUGGGUGGGCAGCCUCUCACUAGUACUUACGGUAGUACCAAAGACGAGUUAAUCAAGGCUCUAUUAUGUAUCCUUAGGCCCUUGAUGCAUGUCUCAUUAUGACCUUAGGACAGCCUUGUGGCAGAGGGAAUGAUUCCAUUUAAUAGACAGUAAAUGGGAUCUCAGUGAGGUUAAGGACAUAAAGCUAAUAAGUGGCAGCACGGGAAUCCAGACACAUGUCUGCCUGAUACCAAACCCAUUUUUUCCCAUCUGCACGCUGCCUUCUGCUGUAAAUAUGUAAAUGUUUCCACAAAAUUCUUUUUCAUACUUUGCCCUGAUAGCAGCAGGGGCUGCACAUCCCAACCUCUUUUCAGCUUAGCUCACCAUAAAAAGCGGGAUCAGAGAUCUACUUCUCAGCUCUUUCUGAUUUCCCCCAGGGAAGUUACAAAAGAAUGACAAAAACUUGGAGAAGGCAGAUAUCAUUAGUAUUAAAGAGAACUGGAGGUUUAGGGGGAAAUAAAGCUGAAUAAAAAACAGCAGGGCUGGCUGAGCGUGGUGGCUCACGCCUGUCAUCUCAGCGCUCUGGGAGGCUGAGGUGGGUGGAUCAUUUGAAAUCAGAAGUUCGAGACCAGCUUGGCCAACAUGGCGAAACCCCAUUUCUACUAAAAAUACAAAAAUUAGCCGGGCGUGGUGGCGGGUGCCUGUAGUUCCAGCUACUCAGAAGGCUGAGGCAGGAGAAUCGCUUGAACCCGGGUGGUGGAAGUUGCAGUGAGCCAAGAUCACACUACUGCACUCCAGUCUGGGUGACGGAACAAGACUCCAUCUCAAAAAAACAAAACAAAACAGGGCCUAUGCAUCCCUGAGAUGUGAAGCAGGGGGAGAUAAGGGAUUUAGAUGUAUAUCCUACUAGGUUUUUGCUGUGUUCUGCCAUGCAGUUGUCUGGGCAGGAUUUAUUUAUAUUUUAAUUUAUUUCAGGGGCCAUGCUAAUCAUCUUUGUAUUGUUCCAAUUUUAGUGUAUGUGCUGCUGAAGCAAGCACUGGGUAAGGUUUAAACUGUCUAGUUCUGUGUGCUGGGGUUUGGCAUUGGAGAAGGCUCUGUGAUGCAUAGACCUUAAAUUAGAGUUAGGUAUAUUAUUAAUCCAAAGUGAUCCUGAAUGCUUUCUAUCAUUUUUUUCUUGUCCUAUUGCACUGGCUAAACUGACUUUUAGUACUACACAGAAUAGAAGCAACAAUAACAAUCAUCCUUGUCUUGUUCCUAACUUUAGUGGACUAUUUACAAUAUUUUACUGAGUUAGAUGCCUUAGGUUCCACGUAGCUGCUCUUUAUGAAAGACCUCACUGGGUUACCCUUCAGUCUUGGAGGAGUCUGGGUAUUGGCCAUGACAUUUGCCAUGAAUGAUGGAGUUCUCUCUGCCAGGUCCUCAUGCCCUGGAGCUGUACGGCUGCACUUCAGCUGCUGCACAUUUGACUUUUUGAGUAGCCCUUGAAUCUCUGCUCUUCCUUGGCCUCUCUAUAGUUUUUGGUAUAAUAGCCUCAGCUUAAGUUUGAGUUUUGUAGGAAAACAAUGGGCCUGUGCUGACAAAGAUACAAAGUCAAGGAACAGGAUUUUUUAUAUCUCAACUAACUUGGUCCUAGCUUUGACAUUUACUUGCCAUAUAACAAUGGAUGAAUAACAGUCUCUUUAAGCCUUAGUUUCAUCCACCGUGAAAUGGGAAAAAUAAUAUCUGUUUCAUAGAGUUGUUUUAGGAUCAUGUAACUUAUGUAAAACACUGAAUAGUUUUCCAGGCAUGAUAUAGGCACUCAAUCUCAUAUUAUGAAUAAGCUUAUGAUGCAUGGGGGAUACUGAUGACAGCUUUCUUCUGUCCAGGCAGGCCCAGCUACAUGGUGGUAUGACCAGUGCAGUCACACAGCCCCAUGCUUAGCAGGGCUCUGCACUUAGUUUAAUGCUCUGCUGUUGCCAUCUUGAAGUUCUUAAUUUUUAAACAAGCAUCCCAUAUUUUGCACUGUUUCUUGCAAACAGUGUAGCCAGUUCUGUCUCCAGGAAUGGAUCCAGCACUAGUACUGGCCCUUCUCUUUGGGAAACAUCCUUCCAUUGAUUUCUUAGGGAGUAAAUCCCUUGAAGAGUAACCUCCCAUAGAAAAAUUAGGGUUAGCACCCUGUGUAUGUUUAUCUCUAACUGUUCCAUUCUCAGUAACCUACACAUCCUCUCUCAUUAAAAAAACAAAACAAAACAAAAAACACUUUAUAUUUUACAGAAGCUAUUAGAUCCAGAGAGGUUGGUAGGGGUGCUGGUGAAAUGGAAUGGUGAUUUGGGAUUUUGGAAUCAGGAAAAAGAUCUAAGUUCAAAACCCUGCUAGUCCCUUUCUGGCCGAGUUACUUGGACAAGGUAAUGUCUCUGUCCUACUGGUAAAGUGUAUGUUGCAGGGGAAUUACAUUCUUUGUUGGUAAAAUAUAUGCCUCAGGGGAAUUAAACAGAUAAUUUAUGUAAAGUGCCUUUCACAGAGAGUCUGGCACAUAGUAGGUGGUCGGUCACUAUUAAUUCUUCCAGCUCUUGCCAGAAAUAACUAAAAUCAGGGCACUAGGACUUCCAAGCCGUGCUGCUACUAAUAAAAGAAAUAAUAUGAUUUAUUUUUUCACAACUGUUUGGGGAAAGGCCUGUGCUUCAUAAAUAUGCGUUGGAAAGUACUUAGCAAAUGAGUAGAAAUAAUAAAAAUAUGUCCAAGUAAA